AUCAAGAAGUAUGGCAGUGACAACUCGUUUGACAUGGUUGCACGAAAAGAUCCUGCAAAAUCAUUUUGGAGGGAAGCGGCUUAGCCUUCUCUAUAAGGGUAGUGUCCAUGGAUUCCGUAAUGGAGUUUUGCUUGACAGAUGUUGUAAUCAAGGGCCUACUCUAACAGUGAUUUAUAGUGAAGAUCAUAUUAUUGGAGCAUAUGCAGAAGAGAGUUACCAGGAAGGAAAGUAUGCUUCCAUCAUCCUUUUUGCACUUCAAGAUACUAAAAUUUCAGAAUGGAAACUAGGACUAUGUACACCAGAAACACUGUUUUGUUGUGAUGUUACAAAAUAUAACUCCCCAACUAAUUUCCAGAUAGAUGGAAGAAAUAGAAAAGUGAUUAUGGACUUAAAGACAAUGGAAAAUCUUGGACUUGCUCAAAAUUGUACUAUCUCUAUUCAGGAUUAUGAAGUUUUUCGAUGCGAAGAUUCACUGGAUGAAAGAAAGAUAAAAGGGGUCAUUGAGCUCAGGAAGAGCUUACUGUCUGCCUUGAGAACUUAUGAACCAUAUGGAUCCCUGGUUCAACAAAUACGAAUUCUGCUGCUGGGUCCAAUUGGAGCUGGGAAGUCCAGCUUUUUCAACUCAGUGAGGUCUGUUUUCCAAGGGCAUGUAACGCAUCAGGCUUUGGUGGGCACUAAUACAACUGGGAUAUCUGAGAAGUAUAGGACAUACUCUAUUAGAGACGGGAAAGAUGGCAAAUACCUGCCGUUUAUUCUGUGUGACUCACUGGGGCUGAGUGAGAAAGAAGGCGGCCUGUGCAGGGAUGACAUAUUCUAUAUCUUGAACGGUAACAUUCGUGAUAGAUACCAGUUUAAUCCCAUGGAAUCAAUCAAAUUAAAUCAUCAUGACUACAUUGAUUCCCCAUCGCUGAAGGACAGAAUUCAUUGUGUGGCAUUUGUAUUUGAUGCCAGCUCUAUUCAAUACUUCUCCUCUCAGAUGAUAGUAAAGAUCAAAAGAAUUCGAAGGGAGUUGGUAAACGCUGGUGUGGUACAUGUGGCUUUGCUCACUCAUGUGGAUAGCAUGGAUUUGAUUACAAAAGGUGACCUUAUAGAAAUAGAGAGAUGUGAGCCUGUGAGGUCCAAGUUGAACUCACAGAUGCAGAACCCAUGGAUACAGAAGGCUAACUGUCUAUCUUUACACUGACAUGGGUAAGUUCAUUUAUUACAAUUUAAUUCAACUAGAUUCAAUUCAAUAAAUGUUUAUUGAUAUUAUCUUUAAGGUUGAGCCAGUGUGUUACUCUCUUAUCAGCUACACAGAUCAUGAAAAAAAUUCCCCCGCACUAAAAAUUUUACAAUUUUAUAAAUAGUGGUGAGGGGAUGGGAGUGUGGGAUAAGAAAAAGUUGACAAGAGAUUAUGUACGAUUGAGUGUGAUAAAUAUAAUGAAACAAUGAAAAAUAAAGUGCUUUAAAAGUUUAGAGAAGGAAAGUAUAGUGUUAAAGGGGUUCGGGGAGAUUUCAUCAAUGGAACGGCACAGGGAAACGGCUUUCAAGGAGAAGAAAUAUUUCACAAAAUGAAGAGACAAAAAGGGCCAACAAAUUCAGCAUAAGACAAUAUAUUAAUGGAGGAAAAGUCAGCAUGUUUGGGAAAUGUGGAGUUCAGGUUAGUGAAGGGCUGGAUCUUUGUAGGCAGAGAUAAAAUGGGCAAGGAACAUUUGCAUGAAGUAAUUUUAUUUAAUUAGGAGCAUUAUGAGGAAUCACAGCAAUUUUUUGAAAGAGUAAUGAUAUGAUCAAAGUUAAUUAAAGUUAUGAUCUUCAGAAAAAUUAAUCUGGCACUGUGUACAGAAUAGAUUGGAAUCAAAAGGAACCUGGAGGUGGGAACACCAGUUGGGAGAAUGCAAUGAUAGCAAGUAUUUGUUGAGCACUAAGUAUGUGAUAGAUUUUCUUAAUCAGUCCUUAUAACAAGCCUAUGAAAUGGGUACUAUCAUUACUGCAUUUUACAAGUGAGGAAACAAAGAAAACAGAGUAAACAUCUGCCAACGUUUAUUGACAGUGCUGAGCAGUGACAGAUAAAUAUUUCGAACCUAGGCAGUUUGAUUCUAGAGGUAAAAUAGUCUAAACAAGAAUUAAACGUUAAACUGGUCUAAUAAAAUCUACUUAUCCAGAGAAUGUUUUUUAAAAGAAACAGGAAAUAUAUGGACUGUAGGAUAGGUGUCAUAAAAAUUUUGUUUCUAAAUCAUUUAGAAUCCACUGCAUGUAUUCCAAAUUACAAUUAUCAGUGACAUUAGAACUUGAUAUGUGAAGUUCUUCAAGAGUACUUUGUGAGACCAGAUCUCCAUUUUUUUCCAAUGGGAAAUUAUUGCAAGUUCCUACAUCUUGAUAUUGCUUUCAUAAUUUAUACUAACAUAAAAUAAUAUUUUUCACUGUUUUGCAAUGUCUUUUUAAUUUCUGUAUUGCAGCUAGAGGAAGUCCAAAGAAAACUUGGAUUUGCUCUUUCUGACAUCUCGGUGGUUAGCAAUUAUUCCUCUGAGUGGGAGCUGGACCCUGUAAAGG